AGUCACUGGAAACUAGGCCGAUAGAGCACCCACCCUGUGGGUGCCUCGUUCUGCCUCCUGCUCCUCGGGCCCAGCCGCCCUGCCAGUCGGGCUGGGUUCCCUCUUGUGUCUUUCCUGAGUCCUUCCGGGGAGGACGAGGCUGUCUUCCUCCCAGCCAACCUUCUGGGCACCUUUCCUCUCUUCCCAAGCUCUGCCUGGGACCCUUUUCCUUCCCCUCAGCCCGUGGCCGUGCUGUGCAGCCGAGCCCCGGCCUGGUCUCUGGCAGCUCAGGGUUCACUCAGGAGGUGCACCAUCCAGUCGUUUCCAGUGUGUUUGCAAUUAUGCAACAAUCGAUGCAAUUCUAGAAGAUUCUUCCCACUCCAGAAAGAAACCCAGGACUCUCCCCCUCGCCUGGCACCCACCCGUCUGCUUUCUGGUCACUGGGUUUCUCUCUGCUGGACGUUGAGCGUGAGUGGACCCCCACGACACGGGUGGGACGUGCUUGCUGUCUGCCCUGCACUGUUUUCCAGGCCUUCCGGUGCGUGGUGGGGCUGCACGCCUCUUCCCGGCCGAACGCCCUUUCCAUGGGUGUGCACGCCACGCCGUCUCUUCAUCCGUUUACCGACGGGCACCUGAGCUGCUUCCGCUUCUCCUGCCAUGAGUGCCUGAGUAUGGGGGUCCCCUGAGGCCUCCCCAGGUGGACCAUCUUGCCAGCACCUUCCUCCCGUGAACGGGUGAAGUAGGCGGCCCCCCCGGCUCAAAUCCAGGGGUCAGUGCCAGGGAUGACCCUGGAAAUAUCUGCUGGGGCGCCUGGUUCUGCGGGGAGUGUCUCCAGCCCUGCCUGCAGGUGCCAUCCCCGCUGUGCCCACUCUGCCGCCUGCCCUUCGACCCCAAGAAGGUGGACAAGGCCACCCACGUGGAGAAGCAGCUCUCAUCCUACAAAGCGCCCUGUCGAGGCUGCAACAAAAAGGUGACCCUGGCAAAGAUGAGAGUGCACAUUUCGUCCUGCCUGAAGGUCCAGGAGCAGAUGGCCAACUGCCCCAAGUUCGUCCCCGUGGUGCCCACAUCACAGCCUAUCCCCAGCAACAUCCCCAACAGGUCCACCUUCGCCUGCCCGUACUGUGGUGCCCGCAACCUGGACCAGCAGGAGCUGGUGAAGCACUGUGUGGAAAGCCACCGCAGCGACCCCAACCGCGUGGUGUGCCCCAUCUGCUCGGCAAUGCCCUGGGGGGACCCCAGCUACAAGAGCGCCAACUUCCUGCAGCACCUGCUUCACCGACACAAGUUCUCCUACGACACCUUUGUGGACUACAGUAUUGACGAGGAGGCCGCCUUCCAGGCUGCUCUGGCCCUGUCUCUCUCUGAGAACUGAAGGGAAGCGCAGCCACCCGCCUGCGUCUGGGGUCAGGGAUGUCCCCGCUCCUGUGUCGCACCUGGCACCUGCUCGGGAGCGCACCUCACCGGACUGAGCUCACAGGAGGAGCCUGCACCCGCGCAGAAGGGGAGCCGGGGCCGAGCCUCCGGGCCUGAAUACGGGCCAGCCGCCGAGGCCGCCAGAGCAGGGCCGCCUGGUCCCACCGGCGUCGCUGGGUUCUUCGGUGCUUCUGGCCGAGCAGGCGGCCUACUUGGGCAGGGCUGGACGCUGGGACCUGGAGCUGCCGCCGUCUCUUCAAAGCCAUGAUACCCCCUCGUGGGAAGAAGGGACCGACGCGCGAGUCGCGCUCCGCAGUCGAGCCGGGAGGAACCCAGGCUGCUGCCCUGCCCAGCCCGACCCUGCCCCGGCCCCACUUCCACCUUGCGCAUUUGGUACUGGCUUUUGUGAUACUUAGGAACCCUGGCAUCUUUUCUAUAUUAUCCAGUGUGAUAAUCUUUUCACGUUUUAUAGAGCAAAGACAGAGCAGUUACUCUUCAUAUUGCAAUAUCUGUGUUUGACUAGGAAUAAUAGUAUUUUUAUGGAACAUUUACAAAAUUAUAUUUUUUAAGAAAACAAUCAAAACAAGCAUUGGGGGAUUGGGGCAAGGAUGGAAGGAGCAGUGGGGCAGCUGCCAGAGCUCAGGCGAGCCAUGGGGUCUGCUGUGGGGUCUGCCCUGGCCACCCACUGUGUGUCUGGGUCCUUGAGGUUUGUACGUUUCUCUUUGAUGACCAGGAAGAAAUCCCAGCACCCCAGCCACAGGCUGUGGCUGCUCCCAGCAGAGGCGGGGCCGGCAGAGAAGGGGCCUCCUCCACCCAGAGUCCUGGCCUUGGCCCGCUGUCACCUUCAAAGCUGACUGUGCCCCGCUGCGGGAGGGGACGGCACCCCAGUGGUGGCAGAGCUUGGGGGCCUGGGCAGGGGCCCGCUUGGCGGGCCGGGCAACACGUCAACAUUCUUUUCUGUUCUUGGCAUUAAUUAUUGCUGUCUUUUUUUUAAAAAAAAAAGUUUAAAUAAAAUGUCUCAGAGCA